ACUCUAUCACCCAGGCUGGAGUGCAGUGGUGCCAUCUCGGCUCACUGCAACCUCCACCUCCCAGGUUCAAUCGAUUCUCCUGCCUCAGCCUCCCGAGUAGCUGGGAUUAUAGGCACCCGCCACCAUGCCCGGCUAAUUUUUAUAUUUUUUAGUAGAGAUGGGGUU